GCUUUCCGGGGUCCCUUUCCCUGGACCAGAUUUUCGCGGGAAGCCGGAUCCUCUCCGUUCCCUUGGAGUGAGCAAGCGGGACAGUUCUGCGGAAAGUUUCCGCCCCCAAUCCCCCAGCCCUGCGCCCGGACUGAAGCGGCGGCCCCCACCUCCAGCAUCCUCGAGCGAUGGUUUCUCCCACAACUACCCCGGUCAGGUCCAGCACUUGGGAGCUGACUGUGCUGGAGGUGACAGGCUUUGCGGGGUCCGCCUGUGUGCAGGAGUCGCAAGGUCGCUGAGCAGGACCCAAAGUUCAGUCGCACUGGGCCGGCUGGACGUUUCCCUGCAACAGGCCCCUGCUGGUGGUUUAGCUCCCGCUCCGUGUUUCCCUCACGCUGGGAUCCUCCUUCCUACUCAAGACCCACGACCUUGACCUGAAGCUUUUGGUUGCCGGGAGGAAAUGGUGGCCCGAGGCAGCCGGGAUGACAGCUCUCCCCAGGAAUCCUGCUGCCUGCUGAGAAACAUGGUCAGCAAGUCCCGCUGGAAGCUCCUGGCCAUGUUGGCUCUGGUCCUGGUCGUCAUGGUGUGGUAUUCCAUCUCCCGGGAAGACAGGUACAUCGAGCUUUUUUAUUUUCCCAUCCCAGAGAAGAAGGAGCCGUGCCUCCAGGGUGAGGCAGAGAGCAAGGCCUCUAAGCUCUUUGGCAACUACUCCCGGGAUCAGCCCAUCUUCCUGCGGCUUGAGGAUUAUUUCUGGGUCAAGACGCCAUCUGCUUACGAGCUGCCCUAUGGGACCAAGGGGAGUGAGGAUCUGCUCCUCCGGGUGCUAGCCAUCACCAGCUCCUCCAUCCCCAAGAACAUCCAGAGCCUCAGGUGCCGCCGCUGUGUGGUCGUGGGGAACGGGCACCGGCUGCGGAACAGCUCACUGGGAGAUGCCAUCAACAAGUACGAUGUGGUCAUCAGAUUGAACAAUGCCCCAGUGGCUGGCUAUGAGGGUGACGUGGGCUCCAAGACCACCAUGCGUCUCUUCUACCCUGAAUCUGCCCACUUCGACCCCAAAGUAGAAAACAACCCAGACACACUCCUCGUCCUGGUAGCUUUCAAGGCAAUGGACUUCCACUGGAUUGAGACCAUCCUGAGUGAUAAGAAGCGGGUGCGAAAGGGUUUCUGGAAACAGCCUCCCCUCAUCUGGGAUGUCAAUCCUAAACAGAUUCGGAUUCUCAACCCCUUCUUCAUGGAGAUUGCAGCUGACAAACUGCUGAGCCUGCCAAUGCAACAGCCACGGAAGAUUAAGCAGAAGCCCACCACGGGCCUGUUGGCCAUCACGCUGGCCCUCCACCUCUGUGACUUGGUGCACAUUGCCGGCUUUGGCUACCCAGACGCCUACAACAAGAAGCAGACCAUUCACUACUAUGAGCAGAUCACGCUCAAGUCCAUGGCGGGGUCAGGCCAUAAUGUCUCCCAAGAGGCCCUGGCCAUUAAGCGGAUGCUGGAGAUGGGAGCUAUCAAGAACCUCACGUCCUUCUGACCUGGGCAAGAGCUGUAGCCUGUCGGUUGCCUACUCUGCUGUCUGGGUGACCCCCAUGCGUGGCUGUGGGGGUGGCUGGUGCCAGUAUGACCCACUUGGACUCACCCCCUCUUGGGGAGGGAGUUCUGGGCCUGGCCAGGUCUGAGAUGAGGCCAUGCCCCUGGCUGCUCUUAUGGAGCCGAGAUCCAGUCAGGGUGGGGGCGCUGGAGCCGUGGGAGCCCGGCCAGGGCAGGGGGCUCGUUGCUGUGGCACCCCCUCUCUGCCAGCACCAAGAGAUUAUUUAAUGGGCUAUUUAAUUAAGGGGUAGGAAGGUGCUGUGGGCUGGUCCCACACAUCCAGGAAAGAGGCCAGUAGAGAAUUCUGCCCACUUUUUAUAAAAACUUACAGCGAUGGCCCCACCAAGGCCUAGACACGGCACUGGCCUCCCAGGAGGGCAGGGGCAUUGGGAAUGGGUGGGUGCCCUCCAGAGAGGGGCUGCUACCUCCCAGCAGGCAUGGGAAGAGCACUGGUGUGGGGGUUCCACCGAGAAGGGGACCUCAUCUAGAAAAGAGGUUACAAACCUACCAUUAAACUAUUUUUCCUAAAACGGAA